CUCUCUCUGGCAAGCCUGCAGGGCAAGUGGCUGAGAAUCAGCCAGAGGGAGGAAAGUGAGGAGGGGUGGACCAGGCCUGGGAGGGUCCUGGGUGGGGGCGCUAAGGAGAGGAGGUGCAGUACAGCCAUGGGGCUCUGGGACUCAUUCGAUCCCCAGGAGGGUGAGGAGUCCGAGGGCUGCUCUGAUUCGCUGAAGUUUGUCUGUGCACUAGCACCCUGGAAUGAGCAGUCUCCAGGCCAUGAAGACCUUGUCCCUGGUCCUGCUGGUGGCCCUGCUGAGCAUGGAGAGAGCUCAGGGUCUGCGCUGCUACAGAUGCUUGGCGGUCUUGGAAGGGGCCUCCUGCAGCGUGGUCUCGUGCCCCUUCCUGGAUGGGGUCUGUGUCUCCCAGAAAGUGAGCGUCUUUGGCAGUAAAGUGAGAGGGGAGAACAAGCUCUCCCUCCUCUCCUGCCAGAAGGACGUCGGAUUCCCCCUGCUGAAACUUACAAGUGCCGUUGUGGACUCCCAGAUCUCUUGCUGCAAGGGAGACCUCUGCAAUGCGGUGGUCCUGGCAGCCAGCAGCCCCUGGGCCCUGUGCGUACAGCUCCUGCUCAGCCUGGGGUCAGUCUUCCUCUGGGCCCUGCUGUGAGGGCCUUUCCCGCCCUCUCCCCCGCAGGCCUACCCUCUGUCCCUGUGCGUCACCAGCUGCUUGGUUUUGAAGAGCUGCCUCACUGAAUUGCAGGAAUUCUGGUGUGGCUUUUCAGCCAUGAGAUCAGGGGAAGGAUGUGGCCAGGGCAGAGGUCGGGGCUUCCCUGUCAGGGAACAUAUCCCUGCUUAAACUCCUUGUCCUCUGGGCCCAGGCCCUCCAGCCCAUGCCCCCCAACAACACCACUUUUUUCAGAGCUGGGCCUCAGAGACCAGGCCCCACCACUGGCUGCUUGGGACCUAGGGUCAUAGAGAAACCGUGGCCCAGGGCGGGAGUCCCCAGCUCCAUCCAGCUUGCCACUAACUUGCCGAGGAGCCAGGGCCAACCCCUCAGCUCUCUGGGCUACCUGAAUCCAAGCAAGGAGGGAACGUGGUCCCAGGGGGCCCUGCUGGCCUCCCACACAGGAUGAGGGCCUCCCUCUCAAGGUCAACAAACAGCCCUUUGCUGACCCACUCAGCGUCAGCACUCGGCUUCUUCCUCACCAUUCCUGAGGCCGCCCACCUGCCACUCUGACCUCAGGCCUCUGCAACAUCCUGCUGGCACCAUGGCCUUGGGGAGGUGCUCCUGGGGCACGGGUGCCCCCCCAGGGACCAGAACCCACAGAGUGCCAGGCUCAUGGCUCUUCUGGCAGAACUCUUGCCAUGUGGCUCCAGGGAACAUCUGAGUAGGGUUGUCAGAGAGCCUCUGGAUGGUCACCAAGAGGCAGAGCUCCUGCGGCCACCAGCCAUCCUGUGGUGUGGGCCAGGCCUGUCAUUUCUGUGCCCUGGCUAGGGCUCCCAUGAUGCCCCGUGUCAGGGGUUAGACUGGUCUCCCCUGGUGGUGGGAGAAAGGGGCUCCUUCAGGACUGCACUCUGGACAGAAAGUCAGGGCUGGGCUCAGAAUGGUCUGGGUGGACGGUCAUCUCAGCCUGGAGUCAGGGCUGGGCUGAGAACGCCCUGGGUGGACGGUCGUCUCAGCCUGGAGUCAGGGCUGGGCUGAGAACGCCCUGGGUGGACGGCCGUCUCAGCCUGGAGUCAGGGCUGGGCUGAGAACGCCCUGGGUGGACGGCCGUCUCAGCCUGGAGUCAGGGCUGGGCUGAGAACGCCCUGGGUGGACGGCCGUCUCAGCCUGGAGUCAGGGCUGGGCUGAGAACGCCCUGGGUGGACGGCCGUCUCAGCCUGGAGUCAGGGCUGGGCUGAGAACGCCCUGGGUGGACGGCCGUCUCAGCCUGGAGUCAGGGCUGGGCUCAGAACAGUCUGGGUGGACGGCUAUUGUCAGGGACCCCAAACAGAGGGACCGGCUGAAGCCAUGGAAGAAGAACAUAAAUUGUGAAGAUUUCAUGGACAUUUAUUAGUUCCCCAAAUUAAUACUUUUAUAAUUUCUUAUGCCUGUCUUUACUGCAAUCUCUGAACAUAAAUUGUGAAGAUUUCAUGGACACUUAUCACUUCCCCAAUCAAUACCCUUGUGAUUUCCUAUGCCUGUCUUUAAUCUUUUAAUCCCAUCAUCUUCGUAAGCUGAGGAGGAUGUAUAUUGCCUCAGGACCCUGUGAUGAUUGUGUUAACUGCACAAAUUGUUUGCAGAGCAUGUGUGUUUGAACAAUAUGAAAUCUGGGUACCUUGAAAAAAGAACAGGGUAACAGCAACGUUCAGGGAACAAGAGAGAUCACCUUAAACUCUGGUUGCCUGUGAGCCAGGUGAAACAGAGCCAUAUUUCUCUUCUUUCAAAAGCAAAUAGGAGAAAUAUCGCUGAAUUCUUUUUCUCAGCAAGGAACAUCCCUGAGAAAGAGAAUGUAUCCCUAAGGGGAGGCCUCUGAAAUGUCUGCUUUGGGGACGGCUGCCUUUUACAGUUGUAGAUAAGGGAUGAAAUAAGCCCCAGUCUCCCGCAGUGCUCCCAGGCUUAUUAGGAUGAGGAAAUUCCCGCCUAAUAAAUUUUGGUCAGACUGGUUGUCUGCUCUCAAACCCUGUCUCCUGAUAAGAUGUUAUCAAUGACAAUGUGUGCCCAAAACUUCAUUAGCAAUUUUAAUUUCGCCCCGGUCCCGUGGUCCUGUGAUCUCGCCCUGCCUCCGUUUGCCUUGUGAUAUCUUAUUACCUUGUGAAGCAUGUGAUCUCUGUGACCCACAUCCUAUUUGUACACUCCCUCCCCUUCUGAAAAUCACUAAUAAAAAUUUGCUGGUUUUACGGCUCAGGGGGCAUCACGGAACCUGCCGACAUGUGAUGUCUCCCCCGGACGCCCAGCUUUGAAAUUUC